CUUGGAUGGGAUUCCGCCUGGUAAUAGCGGUACCGUAGGCUUUUGGCUUCCCGCUCCCUCCUUCUUUCCCCCUUUUGUCUCCGUGCUUCCCAACUGCGCCCCGCCUCUGCUCCCCGUUGACCGCCCCCGUGCCCCAGCCGAAGCCCAGGACCUCCUCCUGAAGAUCCGCCACUGCAGCACCGCCAGGCAGCAGCAUCCCACCUCUUCCGACUCGCGGCAGCCCCACCCAACCCGGGCGGGACGGGACCGACCCCGAGGGUGCAGGCGCGGGUUCCCUGAGGUCCCGGGUCUCUUCACGCUCCCCGGACUCCCAGGCAAUUGUAUUCAUUCAUUCAGCGUCACUGCAACCGUCCAAGCCGGUGGGAGGGGCGAGCAGGGGCAGCGGGUGCCACAGACCCCAGCCAAGACCUCCGCUCCAGAACCCGAGGGCUGCUUUCCCCAGAGGAAGGACAUUUUCUUCGCCAGCCACGAGGAAAUCCGUCCCUGUGCACCCUGUUUCCCAAUGCCACCGACUUCGUGUAAACUCCAGUCCGGAGGACAGGAGAGAGACCCAGGCCUCGCCCCGUGGACAGGCUCGGCGCCACGGCUCCUGCCAGACACACGAGCACACUCUACAAAUCUCGGGGCCCACCGCAUCAAGGAGACAGAAAGAAGCAAACAAAGGAAGGACCUUAUGAAACGCACCCCCAAAGCAACCAACCAAUCCAAGGAAAAAAACAAGUCUCAGGGCUCCAUUGGUUUUCCUGGGUGGGGGGCCCUGACCCCCUGUUCUAGCCCGGCCCAAGAACCCUCCACCACACCCCGGCCUGCUGAAAGGUGCCCUGUCUACCUGAGCAGAGCCUCCCUCUCCAAGGCUCUGUCGCUGUCGCUCCACAACUCCCUCACCCUCUCCCUUUCUCUACUUCCCCCUCCACCUCGCGCUCUACUGUGGUGCUCUCUCUUCCCCCCUCUCUCUCUCCUCCCCCCUUUUCUGUCUCUCUCUCUCUCUCUCUAUCGCUGUCUCUCUCUCUCCCUCUGGUUCUAUUUCUCCAUCCCUCUCUCCCUUGCUCUCCUUCUGCAGCAGGAGGAGCUGCAGACAGAACCCCUCAGACACCGAGUUGUAGAAGGAAGGGCUUUAUUCAGCUGGGAGCAUCCGCAGACUCACGUCUCCAAAAACCAAGCUCUCCGAGUGAGCAAUUCCUGUCCCUCUUAAGGGCUUACAACUCUAAGGGGGUCCGCGUGAGAGGGUCUUGAUGGAUUGAGGAAGCAGAGGGUACGUGACUGGGGGCUGCAUGCACAGGUAAUUAGAUCAGAACAAAACAGGACAGGGAUUUUCACAGUGCUUUUCUAUACAAUGUCUGUAAUCUAUAGAUAACAUAACCGAGUAGGUCAGGGAUCGAUCUUUAACUACCAGGCCCAGGGUGUGGCGCGGGGCUGUCUGCCUGUGGAUUUCAUUUCUGCCUUUUAGAUUUUACUUCUUCUUUCUUUGGAGGCAGAAAUUGGGCAUAAGACAAUAUGAGGGGAGGUCUCCCUUUGAGCUA